AGUGCUGAGGGAGCAAAGUUCAUUUUCUCGGGUAGGAGAAGAUGAUUCUCUUGCAACACGUGCGGAUUGUGACAAAAUCUUUCAUUAACAAGGGGAGUUUCGGUGAAGUGGAGGUUUGGGGAAAGGCGAGGAAGUCGGUCUGGAGCAAGCAAGCAAAGUGCGGAAGCUGUACUGGGAUUCUUCUAGAAAGUGGGGUGGGAAAGGAGCUAGGGAGGGCGUGUGGAGGGACGAGAUCUGUGUCAGAACGUGCGUGUGAGCGGAUACAAAACCCGAGAGAGGCGUGAGCAGCGCUGUGUUUGCGAGCGGGAGCGAGGGGCGCCGGCUGGGGUGUGUGCUCCUGGGAGCCCCCUAAUGAAAGUCUUCAGUAAAUAGUUUUUCUGCAUGCACUGAUUUUCCUGAGGCCAUUGUGGAGAGAGUUAUCUGUGGGCUUGAGAAGCUGCUCUGCCACACCAGUAAGGAUCAGGGAAAGAAAAUACUUAGGCCACACCGUUGCAGUCUUUGAUUGCAUGCCAGUCUGAAGCAUUUUAUGGACCCGUUUUGCCAUAGCUCUUCAGAAACCAGGCUGCUUUCAGGAACAUUGCUGUGGAUUCCCAGGGCCUAUUCCACUAGAAGCAAGAUGGCUGAACUCAAUACUCAUGUGAAUGUCAAGGAAAAGAUCUAUGCAGUUAGAUCAGUUGUUCCCAACAAAAGCAAUAAUGAAAUAGUCCUGGUGCUCCAACAGUUUGAUUUUAAUGUGGAUAAAGCCGUGCAAGCCUUUGUGGAUGGCAGUGCAAUUCAAGUUCUAAAAGAAUGGAAUAUGACAGGAAAAAAGAAGAACAAUAAAAGAAAAAGAAGCAAGUCCAAGCAGCAUCAAGGCAACAAAGAUGCUAAAGACAAGGUGGAGAGGCCUGAGGCAGGGCCCCUGCAGCCGCAGCCACCACAGAUUCAAAACGGCCCCAUGAAUGGCUGCGAGAAGGACAGCUCGUCCACAGAUUCUGCUAACGAAAAACCAGCCCUUAUCCCUCGUGAGAAAAAGAUCUCGAUACUUGAGGAACCUUCAAAGGCACUUCGUGGGGUCACAGAAGGCAACAGACUACUGCAACAGAAACUAUCCUUAGAUGGGAACCCCAAACCUAUACAUGGAACAACAGAGAGGUCAGAUGGCCUACAGUGGUCAGCUGAGCAGCCUUGUAACCCAAGCAAGCCUAAGGCAAAAACAUCUCCUGUUAAGUCCAAUACCCCUGCAGCUCAUCUUGAAAUAAAGCCAGAUGAGUUGGCAAAGAAAAGAGGCCCAAAUAUUGAGAAAUCAGUGAAGGAUUUGCAACGCUGCACCGUUUCUCUAACUAGAUAUCGCGUCAUGAUUAAGGAAGAAGUGGAUAGUUCCGUGAAGAAGAUCAAAGCUGCCUUUGCUGAAUUACACAACUGCAUCAUUGACAAAGAAGUUUCAUUAAUGGCAGAAAUGGAUAAAGUUAAAGAAGAAGCCAUGGAAAUCCUGACUGCUCGUCAGAAGAAAGCAGAAGAACUAAAGAGACUCACUGACCUUGCCAGUCAGAUGGCAGAGAUGCAGCUGGCCGAACUCAGGGCAGAAAUUAAGCACUUUGUCAGCGAGCGUAAAUAUGACGAGGAGCUCGGGAAAGCUGCCCGGUUUUCCUGUGACAUCGAACAGCUGAAGGCCCAAAUCAUGCUCUGCGGAGAAAUUACACAUCCAAAGAACAACUAUUCCUCAAGAACUCCCUGCAGCUCCCUGCUGCCUCUGCUGAAUGCGCACGCAGCAACCUCUGGGAAACAGAGUAACUUUUCCCGAAAAUCAUCCACUCACAAUAAGCCCUCUGAAGGCAAAGCGGCAAACCCCAAAAUGGUGAGCAGUCUCCCCAGCACCGCCGACCCCUCUCACCAGACCAUGCCGGCCAACAAGCAGAAUGGAUCUUCUAACCAAAGACGGAGAUUUAAUCCACAGUAUCAUAACAACAGGCUAAAUGGGCCUGCCAAGUCGCAGGGCAGUGGGAAUGAAGCCGAGCCACUGGGAAAGGGCAACAGCCGCCACGAACACAGAAGACAGCCGCACAACGGCUUCCGGCCCAAAAACAAAGGCGGUGCCAAAAAUCAAGAGGCUUCCUUGGGGAUGAAGACCCCCGAGGCCCCGGCCCAUUCUGAAAAGCCCCGGCGAAGGCAGCACGCUGCAGACACCUCGGAGGCCAGGCCCUUCCGGGGUAGUGUCGGUAGGGUUUCACAGUGCAAUCUCUGCCCCACGAGAAUAGAAGUUUCCACAGAUGCAGCAGUUCUCUCAGUCCCGGCUGUGACGUUGGUGGCCUGAGCUAGGAGGAAAAAGAGCAGUUUUCACUCAGUUUUGGUUCCCUGCCCGAGGUGCUGACCCAAUUCGCUGCCAAAAGAGUGUCAAUCAGAAUAUACAAAUCCCGUAUGGUUGUGUCAUCCUCUCUUAAUCAUUUUUACUAAUUCUAAUAAUCAGCUCUAGCUUGCUUCAUAAUUUUCAUGGCUUUGCUUGAUCUGUUGAUGCUUUCUCUCAUCAAGACUUUGCAGCAUUUUAGCCAGGCAGUAUUUACUCAUUAUUAGGAAAAUCAAGAUGUGGCUGAAGAUCAGAGGCUCAGUUAGCAACCUGUGUUGUAGCAGUGAUGUCAGUCCAUUGAUUGUCUUUAGAGAGUUAAUGUUACAAAAAAGAAUUCUUAAUAAUCAGACAAACAUGAUCUGCUGAGGACACAUGCGCUUUUGUAGAAUUUAACAUCUGGUGUUUUUCUGAAAAAAUAUAUAUACAUAUAUUGCUUUAUUUGAAACAAAUUAAAAUAUGCUGCAUUUGACACCUGGCUAGUUUCUUUUAUUGAUACCCACCUAGUUAUUGAAUGUACUGUUUAGUGCUUUCAAAAAAAACUUUAGAGACUAGAGGUUGUGGUGCAAAGCUGUGUACAAUAAAUACUGUUUCUGUUGAGACAAGUACUCUUUCAGGAAAAUAUAUAUAUGCCCUUUCAAUUAGAUUACACAAAUAGAUGGAUAUGCACCCUGAUCAUCUUAGACACACCAUGUGGCAGUUGGGCAGUUGGAAACAUUGGUUGCAAGUACUACAAACCUCAGCUGAGCCUAGCUUCAACAAUAAGAAUUUAUUGGUUCAGUGAGUGAAAAGUCCAGUUGGUCCAAUUUGAUCAGGAUUUCAGCUCCCAUCUCUUUUUUUUUUUUCUUUUUUCUUUUUCUUUUUUUGAGACAGUCUUGCUUUGUCACCCAGGUGGAGUGCAAUGGCAUGAUCUCGGCUCACUGCAACCUCCGCCUCCUGGGUUCAAGCCAUUCUCCUGCCCGGCCUUCCGAGUAGCUGGGAUUACAGGCAUGUGCCACCACGCCCUGCUAAUUUUUAUAUUAUUAGUACAGACAGGAUUUCACCAUGUUGUCCAGGCUGGUCUCAAACCCCUGACCUCAGGUGAUCCACCUGCUUUGGCCUCCGAAACUGCCGGAAUUACAGGCAUGAGCCACCGUACCCGGCCAGCUCCCAUCUCUUAAUUAUCUUAGCUCUCCUUUCCUCCUUGGGUUGACAUUGCAUUCAGAAUUGUGGCAAAGGGCCACCAUGCUCUUAAGACUCAAGUCUAUUUUCCACACUGUCCAGAGGAGAGAAGUUAUCCUAGUAGCUUCUACACAGAGCAAGUGUCUUUCUCAGAAAUCCCAGCAAAGGUCUUGCAUACCAUUGCUGGUAGGCCUGUCUCUUAAACCAAUCAUGAAAGGGGGGAGAGAAGUGAAUGGGAUGAACUAAUUUGCAUAGACUAAUUAGAGCCCACCCCUGGAGCCUGGGUGUGGCCAUCUUCCCAGAGUUCCUGAGCUAGAUGGAGAAGGGGUACUUCUCAGAAAGGGAAAAUGGAUACCCAAUGGCCCAAACCCAAAAUAGCCCCAGUUCCCCUAACUUUGACUACAGGGCAGUCCAGUUUGGGUGCCGCUUCCGUUGCACUCACAUGUCCUACAUAUCUGUUGACUACUCACAAGUGCAAAUGCUUAUUCUCAACUCAACAUUAACAUUUUUUCUGGCAACCCAGGUUCACUGGUUCUCUUCCACAGAGCGGCCCUGAGCAGCUGAGCCUGCAAGCCACGCAAGCAUCUGUUUCUUCUUUUGCCAAGUACAGGAGGAUGUUUGCUCUCUCUGUAGAGAGCUUUCUGAGGUCUCUGGGUGUACCCAGAGAUUUAAUAGAAAUUCUUAACGUUAAGUCACAUUCCAGGAAGGAAGGAAGAGUUGUUCGUUCAAAUAAGAAAGAUAAAUGUUCGGCACUGUAGGCCCUGUUUACCCCAUCUGAGGCCCUGAAUUCAUAUAUUACAAGACGGAAGGAUUUUGCACAGUUUUUUAUGUAGCAAGAUUUUGCUCACCACUGAAAAAUGUCAGUGUAAAUGUGACCGCUUUAAAGAUGAGUCAAGUAAUUCUUGGAACAGGGAAAAAAAUGAAUUUGCCAGGUCAGGAGUUCACCUGCCUUUGUCAGAGUUGAACCCAACCACUCUUGACCUCGACUCACUCCCUUAGGGUUAAGAAAGCCCAAACACAUUCCUGAGCACAGAGCAAACACUCCCAUGUCACUGAAAAGAAACAAAAGAAUGCUAAAAAGUGCUCAGACCUGAUCACAUUUUUUCCAAUAUUUUUUCCUUUUUUUUUUUUUUUUUGAGACAGGGUCUUGCUCUAUCACCUAGGCUGGAGUGCAUGUUUUUGAGACAGGGUCUUGCUCUAUCACCUAGGCUGGAGUGCAUGAUCAUGGCUCACUAUAGCCUUGAACUCCUGGGCUCAAGCCAUCCUCAGCCUCCCAAGUUGCGAGGACUACAGGUGUGCACCACAACGUCCCAGCUACUUUUUAAAUUUUUAGUAGAAACGAGGUCUCACUAUGGUGCCCAGACUGGUCUCGAACUCCGGAGCUCAAGUGAUCUUCCUGCUUUGGCCUCCCAAAGUGUUAGAAUUACAGGCAUGAGCCACCUCGCCUGGCUGGUUUUUGCCUUUCUUAUAGACCCUGGGCAUGUAAGCAUUUAUUAGUUUGCAUUUUUGAAACAGUAAUUUCAAUAUUUUAGUGCCAAUGUCAGGCCGCUUAAACACUGUAUUACAUAUCUUCAUCUGUCUGGUGGAACUAUUGGUGUGAUCCUAGAGAACUGAGUCCUAUUCUGCCAUUCAUUUAAAGUGUUUUAAACUCUAAUCUCUCUACUUAAUGCACAGUAGUCAGAUUAUUCUCUUAAACAUUUGCCUAGUAGAGGUUAAAAUAGUUUAAUCCUUAUGAAGAUGGAAUAACUUCAAACUCACAUUGUGGCACUUAGAUCUUCCACCAAGACUUCAUCCGUGAAAUCCACACCUCCCUGUUGGGUUCCCAAUUACAUUCCAAAUUUACAUUUCUUUUGAGAAUCUCUGCAUACUCCAGCUCUGUCCUGUUGAUCCUAUUCUAGAAGUGCUUAAUGCAGCAAGACACAGAAAGUUAAACGCAAAUUGCUGCAAAAUUCACCCUCAGUGGAGGACUAGAAACACAACAUGUCCAAUUUAAAGCUCAGUUCACAAGCAGUUCAAUUCUGCUGGCAUCAGAAAAGGAGAUUCUAAUUAAACAUUCUUAGGGAAGGACAUCAAAUGAGGUUAAUGGGAAACGUUACCAGAUUAAAAGCAGUUUUUUGACAAAGUAACAGAUUUGGAAAUUCUGACUCUCUGAAAGCCUUGAUUUGAACCUCAAACUUGAUUUCACCAUGAGAAGUGGGGAUCAAGGGCCUGCGCAGUUCUUUUCCUAAAUCGAUUCGGUGCUCCCCACCCCGACGCAGGCACAGGUCCGCAACCAGAUAGGGAGAUGCCUGAAUUUCAGGCUACCUUUGACAAAGCUUUCUUCCUCCCUCCCUCCCUUUGCACGCUGCAUCCCACGCUGCCUGCUUAAAGCGCCCUCAUGUGUCUACAGAUGGUAAAACGUUUAUUUCUCAACAGACAUUCCAGUGAUAGCAUCCAAUGACCUAUGUAACGGCACCCUUUUUUGCUGUACGCGUUUUUUGAGAUGGAGUCUCGCUCUGUCGCCCAGGCUGGAGUGCAGUGGCGCGGUCUCGGCUCACUGCAAGCUCCGCCUCCCGGGUUCACGCCAUUCUCCUGCCUCAGCCUCCCGAGUAGCUGGGACUACAGGCACCCGCCACCACACCUGGCUAAUUUUUUGUAUUUUUAGUAGAUACAGGGUUUCACCGUGUUAGCCAGGAUGGUUUUGAUCUCCUGACCUCGUGAUCCACCCCCCUCGGCCUCCCAAAGUGCUGGGAUUACAGGGGUGAGCCACUGCGCCCGGCCCCAGUCACUUGUUCUUAAGUUUCUUAAGCAAACUAUAAAAUAGCAAAAGACCAAAAAAAAAGGAAAAAAAGCAGUUCGCCUAAUACAUUGUUCCAGCAUUUCCUUGAAAGUACUGAGCCAUCUCAAUUGCUCUGAUUUUGUGAGAAAAUUAUGAAGAGUUGCAAAGUCCCAGUGAUUCUCUUGUUACUUAGCUAAGAAUUUGAAAUGUAAUUUAAAUACUAUUCUUUACAAUCCAUUAUAAGGAUUUUAAAAUCUUUUUGCUUCUUUAAUAAAUUCUAACAAAGU